AGGGAGGGGAGGGAGGGGCGGGGGCCGGGCCUCCCAGCGCGGUACGCGGUGCCUUUUGAGCUCCUUGUCCACGCUCCGCCCCGGUGGGAACGGCCGCGCGCUCCCCGCAGGUGGUCAUCCGCCGCCUGCCUCCGGGCCUCACCAAGGAGCAGCUGGAGGAGCAGCUGCGCCCGCUGCCAGCACACGACUACUUCGAGUUCUUCGCCGCCGACCUGAGUCUUUAUCCUCAUCUCUACUCAAGAGCAUACAUUAAUUUUAGGAAUCCUGAUGACAUCCUUCUUUUUAGAGAUCGUUUUGAUGGAUAUAUCUUCCUUGACAGCAAAGUGGCUCACACCUGUAAUCCCAGCACUUUAGGAGGCCAAGGCGGGUGGAUCACGAGGUCAGGAGUUCGAGACCGGCCUGAGCAACAACGUGAAACCCUGUCUCUACUAAAAAUACAAAAAUUAGCCAGGCAUGGUGGCAGGCGCCUGUAGUCCCAGCUACUCGGAAGACUGAGACAGGAGAAUUGCUUGAACCUGGGAGGCGGAGGUUGCAGUGAGCCGAGAUCAUGCCACUGCAUCCCAGCCGGGGCGACGGAGCAAAAAAAUAUGCCUAGAAUAUCCUGCAGUGGUAGAGUUUGCUCCAUUCCAGAAGAUAGCCAAAAAGAAGCUGAGAAAAAAAGAUGCCAAGACUGGAAGCAUCGAAGAUGAUCCAGAAUAUAAGAAGUUUUUAGAAACCUACUGUGUGGAGGAAGAGAAGACCAGUGCCAACCCUGAGACUCUGCUGGGGGAGAUGGAGGCGAAGACAAGAGAGCUCAUUGCUAGAAGAACCACACCUCUUUUGGAAUAUAUUAAAAAUAGAAAAUUAGAAAAGCAGAGAAUUCGAGAAGAGAAGCGAGAAGAACGGAGGAGGAGAGAGUUAGAAAAGAAACGUUUGCGGGAAGAGGAAAAAAGAAGAAGAAGAGAAGAAGAAAGAUGCAAAAAAAAAGAGACAGAUAAACAGAAGAAAAUUGCAGAGAAAGAAGUAAGGAUUAAGCUUCUUAAGAAACCAGAAAAGGGAGAGGAACCAACCACAGAGAAACCAAAAGAAAGAGGAGAGGAGAUUGAUACUGGAGGUGGCAAGCAGGAAUCCUGUGCCCCCGGUGCAGUCGUAAAAGCCAGGCCCAUGGAAGGCUCGCUGGAGGAGCCCCAGGAGACGUCACACAGCGGCAGUGAUAAAGAGCACAGGGAUGUGGAGAGAUCUCAAGAACAAGAAUCUGAAGCACAAAGAUACCAUGUGGAUGACGGCAGGAGGCACAGAGCUCACCACGAGCCUGAACGGCUUUCCAGAAGGAGUGAGGAUGAGCAGAGAUGGGGGAAAGGACCUGGCCAAGACAGAGGGAAGAAGGGGAGCCAGGACAGCGGGGCUCCGGGGGAGGCCAUGGAGAGACUGGGAAGAGCGCAGAGGUGUGACGACAGUCCAGCACCCAGAAAAGAGCGACUGGCAAACAAGGACCGGCCAGCCUUGCAGCUGUAUGAUCCAGGAGCUCGCUUCCGAGCGCGAGAGUGUGGCGGAAACAGGAGGAUCUGCAAGGCAGAAGGUUCGGGGACUGGUCCUGAGAAGAGGGAAGAGGCAGAGUGAGUCACUGCACGCACCUGGCCUCCAUGGACGAGCAAGGGCAUCCCAGAAACGUGUAAAUGACCCCGAGUGUGACUGGGAAGGAGAACUUAUUCCUUACCAGGAAACUGGAAGCUAAAAAUACAGAGGGUGACGUAGAAACACGCAGAAACCAUUCUAAAGAAAGUAGUGAUCUUGUAUUAAAUUGAGCAGAAUUCUCACAGAUUUUACCAUUCCUGUUAUAAACUAGUAUUUGUUGUUUAGCCAAAACAGAAAAUGAUUUCCACUGGACAGUAGAAAAAUAUGUGUAAAAUAGGGAAGAAAGUUAGUAUUGGAUCAGUGUGAGUCCUGAAGCACUUUCAGUGCUGUGAGAACGACAUCCACUUUGGGUUUCAUUCGUUUGUAAGCAGAGGAGCUGUCAGUCACUCGUGCUUCUCGGUGGCCUCUGAGCCAUGGUGUCGAGUGAAGAGUAGUUCUUGUUUGUUACAACCUUUGUGAGUCAGCCAUGCCCGCAAAGCGUGCUGUGUUUUAGUCCUGGUAGGAAUAUUUAUCAGAGUUCACACUAUAUAAAACCCAACAGCUUCAACUAUUGCCCUUUCAACAGUUUUGCCACUGACCGGAUAGAAACGGUUUCAGUCUCUGGAUGGAUGUGUUUGUGGUUUGUAACCAUUACGGUUUAAACCAUGGUUUAAGAAUUUGCCCAAAUAACAGAAAUUUUGUUCGGGAAGGGAUAAACUAGAUAUAGCAUACAGAGCCUGUUUUUGAGUUUUAGAUACUUUAUUUGUAAAUAACUUAAAAUAGCUUUCUGAAACCGUGCAUUCUGUAGUUUCUUCCUUUCAGUGAAAUUGCUAAAUGUCAAUGUAUUUUUGGCACUGCGAUUUUAACCAUUUAUUAAAUAAAAAUUUUGUUAAAGAAGUACUGAAA